ACUAGCGCUGCUGGCGGCCCCGGCGGCCGGGCGUGCUGCCUGCAAGAUGUCCGUGCGCCGCGGCCGGCGGCCGGCGCGGCCGGGGACCCGCCUCUCCUGGCUGCUGUGCUGCAGCGCCCUGCUGUCCCCGGCCGCGGGCUACGUGAUCGUGAGCUCCGUGUCUUGGGCCGUCACCAACGAGGUGGACGAGGAGCUGGACAGCGCCUCCACUGAGGAGGCUAUGCCCGCGCUGCUAGAGGAUUCGGGCAGCAUCUGGCAGCAAAGCUUCCCCGCCUCUGCCCACAAGGAGGACGCGCACCUGCGGCCCCGGGCGGGCGCCGCCCGGGCCAGGCCGCCCCCCGCGCCACCCGGGAUGUUCUCCUACCGGCGCGAGGGCGGCCAGACGGCCAGUGCGCCCCCGGGCCCUAGACUGCGCGCCGCCACCGCCCGCUCCCUGGCCCAUGCCAGCGUCUGGGGCUGCCUGGCCACCGUGUCCACCCACAAGAAGAUCCAAGGACUGCCAUUUGGGAACUGCCUGCCCGUCAGUGAUGGCCCCUUCAACAAUAGCACUGGGAUUCCUUUCUUCUACAUGACAGCCAAGGACCCCGUGGUGGCUGAUCUGAUGAAGAACCCCAUGGCCUCGCUGAUGCUGCCAGAAUCAGAAGGGGAGUUCUGCAGAAAAAACAUCGUUGAUCCGGAAGAUCCCCGAUGUGUCCAGUUAACGCUCACUGGCCAGAUGAUCGCAGUGUCUCCAGAAGAAGUAGAAUUUGCCAAGCAAGCCAUGUUUUCAAGGCACCCAGGGAUGAGGAAGUGGCCUCGUCAAUAUGAAUGGUUCUUUAUGAAGAUGAGGAUAGAACAUAUCUGGCUUCAGAAAUGGUAUGGAGGCGCAUCCAGUAUUUCAAGGGAGGAAUAUUUCAAAGCAGUUCCCAGAAAGGCCUGAUGGAGUGAGAAGAAAGUCCUUGGUGUUUGCACUUAAAUGAAAACCUUUUCAGUGAUGCAGCCAGACAGCUAUUGACCACUGUCUCUUUGUUGAAGGGUUCAUAGCAGCCCUGCCAUCCCUGCAGCAGAAUGAGAGAGGGUGAACAGGGAACUCUAUGCUAGAUUUGAGAUUAAAGUGGUCAUUUGCAGAUCUCCAACUCACACAGAUACUUCACGUAGAUAGUCUUUAUUCCAUUGUAUUCAAUCCAGACUCAUCGAUUCAGAAAUCAUAUAAUAGCUGGUGGUCAAAAUGACAUGUUGAGAUCAUUGUUGUUUCAUUGUUUAAGGAAAAAAAAAAAUGCCUGUACCUACAAUGUGAUUGCUUUGUAUUGUGAGAGUAUCUUUGUUGCUUGCUCUGCCAAAUGCAGUCUUGGUUCUAAGUUCACUGUGACCACGAAGCAGCUGACUGUGCAUCACGCAGUCACAAUAUUGUUUUUAGGGUGAGGGUGGAGGACUGUGUGUCCGUGGAUUACUCCUCCUGCUGGUGGAUUGCAGAUGCAUUAUUAGGUCAUACUGGCUAGAAUGCAGCUUUUCUCCCACCAUAACAUGAAAACAGUGUAAGAACAUAGGGUGCUUUGUGCAUAGCCCUUCUCUAUGUAAGCAGCCAUGGCAGUCAUUAAAGAGAAAGGAGUAGCUUUGACAUUAAGCUCCCCAGAUCCCUGCUGCUCAUACUUCUGGCAAGGGUUCCCCUCUCUCAUGCAUGAACAGGGGCAUCCAAAAUAAGAAGCUCUCCAUUCUGUGGUGGGGAAAGCGGAGAGGGGAGUGGGUGAAGCUGGGAAAGUAAAGGCAGCACGUUACAGAAGGAAGAAAGGAAGCCAGUAACUGAGGGCCCACUGCCUGCCCGGCCCUGGGCCAGGCCCUCAACAGAAGCCAUCUCAUUUAAGCCCUGCAACCAAUGAGAUGCACGUCAUCAUUGGCUCUUACAGACAAGAAAACUAGACUCAGAGGGGCUGAGUCCACAUCCCAGACAGCUCACUGCAGACACAGGUGGAGUGGUUCCUACAAGACAUCCAGUUUUAACAACAAAAGAGUUAUUGAAAUGCAUGGGUAGAAAUUGAACCAGGAAAAUCAGUAAAGUGAUUGUAAAAAAGAAGGACUAGCUUGCCUGGAGAUGAUGUUUCUUGCUUUUGGAAAAAAAAAAAAAGUCUCUGAAAUUUGAUUCUUACUACAGAUUUAAAACUUUCUACAUAUUAUAUGUAGGAGCUCCUAGUGUUUUUGAGAAAUUAGACUGUACCUGUGUACACUUCUAAGGUCUACAUGGACCUAUGUAUAUAUAUCUAAGACCUCUGAUCAUUAAAACCUAUAAAGGGUUGAGCUGUCCCAAGUUUUCUGUCUUUCUGUAAUGGCUACAAACUUUCUUUGGUAGGUUAGGGAGGUUGUAUAACAUAAAAAACACAUCACUAUAUGUAGGAAAUAUACAUUUUUCAAGUAAAUAAGAGUGUUAUUAAUGAUUAUGAACUUUUGCUUAACAAAAUAACAUACGACGAGAGCUUGAGUUGUCAAAAUAUAUUUUAAUUAUCUAUUGCUAAAAACAUAGUAAGAUGCAGAGAAUUCUUUAUUUGUCAUAAGCCAGUCCUCAAAAGAGUUCCUAACAGUAGUGAUUUCUAAUAUAUAAGAAUAAGGUACUUCUGAGGGAAUUUUAUAUUUUCAGAGUUUAAAAUUAUUGCUACUCCCAAUUUAGAAAAAUGGGGAGAAAGCUGGAAGAACAAAUGACAUGCUCAAAUGUAUUGCAUAAGUCAACCUCACACCUUAAUACUGGGAGCUUCUCUGCCUCCUGAUCCUGUCUUGCAGAUAAGGUCCCCUGGCUAGGUUUGCGUUUAUAGUCAGGUUCCAUUUAGCUCAUUAAAGGUCACUGCUGCUUCAAAGGACUUUGCCCAGUGGAUGCCAUUCAUAACCACUGAUGAAUGUUAUCAGCUAUUUAUCCAAAUUACAGGAAAUGAAACCUGAAAAGGUUGGGUAAGAAUAGUGUUGAAAAUUCACAGUUUUAAGUUUGAUGGUCUCCAUUCAGGCAAGUGUGUUUCAGCAAAUCUCUAGAAAUUUACAUUGAUUAAAAUGUUAGAGGCUGUUCUGGAAGUUCUAGACAUGGCAAUAAGGCAAGAAAAAGAGAUUAAAUGCAUACAGAUCGAAAGAAAAAAAAAGUACCCCUAUUUAGAGAUGAGAGGAUUGCCUACAUAGAAAUUCCAAAUAAUCUAUUUUUUUUAAAAAAAAACUCUGGAACUAGUAUGUGAGUGCAACAAGGUCUCAGGACACAAGAUCAGCAUACAAAAGUCAAUUGCAUUUCUCUAUGCUAACGAUGAACAUGUGGGGAAAAAAACUAAAAACACAAUACCAUUUGCAAUCACUCCAAAGUGAAAUACUUCCGUAUAAACAAAACUUACCCAGGACCUAUGUAGUGAAAAUUUUUAAAUGCUAAGAAAAGAAAUUAAUGACCUAAACAAAGAAAGAGAGAUACCAUGUUCUUGGAUUGGAAGAUACAAACAGUAAAGAUAUCAGUUCUCCCCAUCUCCAUCUCUAGGUUUAAUGCAAUUCCUAUCAAAAUCUCAACAAGGAUUUUGUAGACCUAUACAAGCUUAUUUUAAAAGUUACAUGGAAAGGCACAGGCAUUGAAAUAGCUAAAACAGUCUUGUAAAAGCAGAAUAAGGUAGGAGAAAUCAUUCUAUUUAAUAUAGAGUUAUGAUGUAGCUACAGUAUUCAAGAAGUGUGGUAUUUGGUGGAGGCAUAGAAACACAUUGAUGGAACAGAAUAGGGAAUCUAGAAAUAGGCCCACACAAAUAUGCUCAACUGAUUUUCUUUUACAAAAGUACAAAACUAAUUCAACAGAGGAUAGCCUUUUCAAUAAGUGUGGAGUAAGUGGACAUCCAUAGGAAAAUAAAAUGAACCUUGGACUAAACUUCAUACCUUAUGCAAAAAUUAACUCAGAUCAUAUCUGUAAAAAUAAAAUGUAAAACUAUAAAACUAUAGGAUAUAGAAAAUCUUUUGGAACUAGGGCUAAGCAAAGGGUUGUUAGACUUGAUACCAAAAGCACAAUUCAUAAAAGAAAAUUUGAUAAAUUAAACUUCAUCAGAAUUUAAAACAUUUGUUCUGCAAAAGACCAUGUUAAAAGGCCGAGAAGACAGGCCACAUACUGGGAGAAAAUAUUUCCAAACCACAUAUCCAACAAAAGAUUAGUAUCUAGAAUAUAUAAAGAACUGUCAAAACUCAACAGCUAAAAAAUUCUAAUUAGAAAAUGGAGCACAUGAACAGACAUUUCACUGCAGAGGAUAUAAAAAUGGCAAAUAAGCGCAUGAAAAGACAUGAAAAGACAGUCAACAGCACUAGUCACUAGGGGAACUGCAAACUAAUACUACAAUGAGAUAUCACUACAUAGCUACCAAAAUUGCUAAAAUAAAAAAUAAUGAUAACACCAAACGCUGACAAGGAUGCAGAUAAACCGGGUCAGUCAUACACUAGUGGUGGGAAUAGAAAAUGGAACAGCCACUCCGCAAAACCAUUUGCCAGUUUCUCAUAAAACUAAACAUACAACUGCCAUACUGACCCUCAAUUGCUCCUGGGCAUUUAUACAAGAGAAAUGAAAAGAGGUUCACACAAAAACUUGUGCAUGAAUGUUCAUAUCAGUUUUAUCCAUAAUGUUCAAAAACUUGGAGAAAUCAGAUGGCCUUUAACGGGUGGCUGGUGAAACAGUGGAUGGUGCCUCUAUGCCCGGAAUACUACUCAGCGAUAAAAAAGAACUAAUUACUGACAUGGGCAACCACUGGGAUGAAUUCCAGAGAAUUGUGCUGAGUGAGCAAAGCCAAUCAUAAAAGUUUGCACACUGUAUGAUUCCAUUUACAUAACAUUUUGAAAUGCAAAAUUAUAGGAAUGGAGAAUAGAUUAGGGGUUGCCAGGGAGGAGUGGGGAGAACAAGAGAGUUGGGCAUAACUAUAAAAGGAUAGCACAAGAGAUCCUUGUGGUGAUGGACAUAUUCAGUAUCUUGACCAAAUCAAUGUGAAAAUCCUGGUUGGGAUAUUGUACUGUAGUUUAGCAAGAUGUGCCAUUGGGGAAAACUGGGUAAAAAGAACACAGGAUCUCUGUAUUAUUUCUUACAACUGCAUGUGAAUCUACAGUUAUCUACAACUAUCUCAGAAUCUACAAUUAUCUCUGAGUAAAAAGCUUAACAUAAACAAGAUUUAGGGCUUAGCUUAAUAAAGCAUUUAUACUCUCUCUCUUAUUAGUCCCUAAUAAAAUGAGGAACUGAGCUAUAAGCCAAAACCUAGUACAAAGAGACAGCAUUUCAUUUGUUAACCGUUAAUAUAUCCAUUUGCAGAAGAGGUGUAAAAUUCUUUAAAAUUUUCCUAAAUAUGUUCAAUUUAAUGUUAAAUACAAAUUAACAAGAAUUCAACAAAUCUGCUGUAUAGAUUUUAAGUGGGUCACUUAGGAGGAGAGGACAUCUUCGAAUUUCUGAUAUAAACACGUUGAGUAAGCUAUAGGUGUAUAUAAGUAUCCAAGUGUGUAUAUAAUGAUUCUCCACUGAUUUUAUAGAGAAGAACUAUAUUUCCAGUAAUCUUCCCCUAAAUAUUGUGGGAAAUAAUUCUGUUUUAGUGAAUAAGCUAAUUAAAGUCUAUCCAGACCACCAUGUUUUUAUUUACAGUGACUAUAUAUAUCCAUGAUUUUGACAUAGAGUAUAAUUCUGAUGUUACUUAUUUCAAUAUGCCUUGUAUAUAUUAGCUGUUUAUAAGAGAGUCGCUUUUUGGUUGAAAAGUAUUUCUAGGCUGAGCAAGGUAGCUCAUGCCUGUAAUCCAAACACUUUGGGAGGCCAAGGCAGGAGGAUCACUUGAGGUCAGGAGUUCAAGAGCAGCCUGGGCAACAUAGUGAGACCUCAUCUCUACAAAAAAUAUUUAUUAAAAAAAAAAAAAAAAAAGCCCAGCAUGGUGGUGCACACCUGUAGUUCUAGCUACUCAAGAGGCUGAGGUGGGAGGAUUGCUUUGAGGCCAGGAGUUUGACCUCCUGAGCUGUGAUCAUGCCACCACACUUGAGUGAUAGAGUGAGACUUUGUCUCUUAAAAAAAAAAAAAGGUAUUUCUACAAUUUUUCCAAAAAGUCUGUAUUUAUUUAAAUAAUUGAACUAUCAAAUACUGUUCUGAAAAUAAAACCUCUCUAGGAUAAUUUAUUGAUGCUUAUUUGAUUGCUAUAACAGAAAGUCAAUUAUUGUACAAUUUGAAUUGUAAUGAUGUGAUUAUUUGUGCCAUGUAAUGCAUGUAAAAUGUAAAAUCUGUUUUCAAAACUAGAUCUAUUUAACCAAAGACUAUUUCAUUCCUGAUAUGAUUUGUGUGCUUGAUUAAAUGAAUUUAUGAUAUUGA